GCUUCUUCGCCAGAACCAACCGGUUGCUUGCUGUCCCAGCGGCGCCCCCUCAUCACCGUCGCCAUGCCCGGAGGUCUGCUUCUCGGGGACGUGGCUCCCAACUUUGAGGCCAAUACCACCGUCGGCCGCAUCCGUUUCCACGACUUUCUGGGAGACUCAUGGGGCAUUCUCUUCUCCCACCCUCGGGACUUUACCCCAGUGUGCACCACAGAGCUUGGCAGAGCUGCAAAGCUGGCACCAGAAUUUGCCAAGAGGAAUGUUAAGUUGAUUGCCCUUUCAAUAGACAGUGUUGAGGACCAUCUUGCCUGGAGCAAGGAUAUCAAUGCUUACAAUUGUGAAGAGCCCACAGAAAAGUUACCUUUUCCCAUCAUCGAUGAUAGGAAUCGGGAGCUUGCCAUCCUGUUGGGCAUGCUGGAUCCAGCAGAGAAGGAUGAAAAGGGCAUGCCUGUGACAGCUCGUGUGGUGUUUGUUUUUGGUCCUGAUAAGAAGCUGAAGCUGUCUAUCCUCUACCCAGCUACCACUGGCAGGAACUUUGAUGAGAUUCUCAGGGUAGUCAUCUCUCUCCAGCUGACAGCAGAAAAAAGGGUUGCCACCCCAGUUGAUUGGAAGGAUGGGGAUAGUGUGAUGGUCCUUCCAACCAUCCCUGAAGAAGAAGCCAAAAAACUUUUCCCGAAAGGAGUCUUCACCAAAGAGCUCCCAUCUGGCAAGAAAUACCUCCGCUACACACCCCAGCCUUAAGUCUCUUGGAGAAGCUGGUGCUGUGAGCCAGAGGAUGUCAGCUGCCAAUUGUGUUUUCCUGCAGCAAUUCCAUAAACACAUCCUGGUGUCAUCACAGCCAAGGUUUUUAGGUUGCUAUACCAAUGGCUUAUUAAAUGAAAAUGGCACUAAAAGUUUCUUGAGAUUCUUUAUACUCUCUGCCUUCAGCAAUCAAUUCCAUUCAUACAUCAGCACUCUGCUGGUUCUGUUUGAAAUAUGUUCUGUAUUUAAAACUCAAAUCUUGUUGGAUCUCUGCAGGGCUUGUGACCAAUGAAGUCAUAUUUGUUGAUGGUUGACAAAGCUUGCUUCACUCCAUCAGAGAAUGACUAUCAAUUUUUUUUUAACUGUCCUAUCACGUCCUCUCCUGUCACCCAUUUUGAAGAGUGGCAGAACUUGAAGUUCAACUUCCUCUGUAAAUAUCCAAGUAUAAAGCCCAGGAACUUCUAGAAUAACCCAGAUGCGCUUUAAUUUUUUUUAAUAUGUUUUGAUCACAGAACUUCUAGAAUAACCCAGAUGCUCUUUCAUAUUCUUUUAAUACAUCUUGAUCACAGCUGGGGGAAAAAAAGCUUUUUAAUUCUAUACCUUCCUAGUAGAUAAGUGAAGAGCAGGGAAAGAGACCUUUAAAUAUUUUGCUAUAAAAAAAUUUGUGAUAAGUUUCUAUCAAAAUGGGGAGAUUGCAGAAAAGGCUUCCCUUGGCUCCCAAGGAGGUGUAGCAGGUGUGAGCAAUAUUAGUGCCAUGUGCCUUUCACACAGGGUUUGCAUUUAUCAGUCUGUUUUCCGAUGAUGUGUACAUGAAAGAGUACACCAUGUGAAGAGAAGAGAGAAUGAUUGAAAAUGUUUUAGUAUAGAACUCUUCUUGCAGUGGGUUGCUAUUUUCUAGAUUUUACUUUUUAGGGAACAAAAUAAAAUCCUUUGUUAAAACUGGGUCAGAGAA